ACGUCAGAGGGUCGCGCCGCUGCAGGAACCCGCUCUGCCUGAGCUACCGCGAGUCGUAGAAAAUUACGUAAUGAUAGGGGGCCGGUCAGAGUGAGGGCACCUGAGGUACACGAAAUCCCUCCGGCUUGCCCACUUCCUCGGACUUUCCACCAAUCAGGAGCUUCCUCCCCAGCACCAACCAAUUGUGGGAGAGAAGUUUUCUCUGUGCUACAAGCCCGGAAUUUCAUUCAUACCCAGCUACGCUCCGAAUGAGGGAGCAGAGGUACAGCGGCCGAAUGAGCGGGAACAGUUAUUCCACGACAGGUGUACAUCAGACGCAUUGCUUAGGCCUCUUAUUUUACGUUCUCCAAGCAACUCCAUAAGACAACUGUCUCGGAAAGGCUACAGUGAUGACAGACCGACUUAAGUUCGGAUUCGGCUUCCACCGCUUCUUAGUGGUAUGCAAAGAAGCCUUUUCACCCUGAUGUCCUUAGAGAUAAUAUGGAUCAGUCCAGAGUUCUCCUCUGGGUGAAAGCAGAACCCUUUAUAGUGGGUGCCUUGCAGGUCCCCCCUCCAUCCAAGUUUAGUCUUCACUAUCUCAGGAAGAUAUCCACCUAUGUGCAAAUCCGGGCCACAGAAGGAGCUUACCCGCGCCUCUACUGGUCUACAUGGAGGCACAUCGCUUGUGGGAAGCUGCAGUUGGCCAAGGACCUGGCGUGGCUUUACUUCGAAAUAUUUGAUAGUCUUUCAAUGAAGACACCUGAGGAGCGCCUGGAAUGGUCUGAGGUUCUGUCCAACUGCAUGUCUGAGGAGGAAGUUGAAAAGCAGAGAAAUCAGCUUUCAGUGGACACGCUACAGUUUCUGCUCUUCUUAUACAUUCAACAGUUGAACAAGGUCUCCCUAAGGACAUCUUUGAUUGGCGAAGAGUGGCCCAGUCCCAGAAACAAAUCUCAGUCUCCUGACCUGACUGAAAAAUCUAAUUGUCAUAAUAAGAACUGGAAUGAUUACAGUCACCAAGCUUUUGUCUAUGAUCAUCUGUCUGAUCUCCUCGAGCUGCUUUUAGAUCCAAAACAACUCACUGCAUCAUUUCAUUCAACCCAUAGUAGUCUAGUGUCUCGAGAAGCUGUUGUGGCGCUCAGCUUCCUUAUUGAAGGUACAAUAAGUAGAGCCAGGAAGAUCUAUCCACUUCAUGAACUUGCACUGUGGCAACCACUGCAUGCAGAUAGUGGCUUCUCAAAGAUCUCUAAGACUUUCUCUUUCUACAAACUGGAAACCUGGUUGAGGUCCUGUUUGACUGGGAAUCCAUUUGGUACAUCAGCUUGCCUCAAGUCUGGAAAGAAAUUGGCUUGGGCUCAUCAAGUUGAAGGGACCACCAAAAGAGCUAAGAUUGCUUGUAAUACUCAUGUGGCCCCUAGGAUGCACCGACUGGUAGUGAUGAGCCAGGUUUACAAGCAGACACUGGCUAAGAGCUCAGACACUCUGGCGGGGGCACAUGUAAAGAUUCAUCGUUGCAACGAAUCUUUUAUAUAUCUGCUCUCUCCCUUACGAUCUGUGACAAUUGAGAAGUGCAGGAAUAGCAUCUUUGUCUUGGGCCCUGUAGGGACUACACUUCACCUCCACAGUUGUGACAAUGUUAAAGUCAUUGCUGUUUGCCAUCGUUUGUCCAUCUCUUCUACAACAGGUUGCAUCUUUCACGUUCUUACGCCUACACGCCCACUUAUUCUCUCUGGGAACCAGACAGUAACUUUUGCCCCUUUUCAUACACAUUACCCAAUGCUAGAGGACCAUAUGGCCAGGACUGGCCUUGCUACAGUGCCUAACUAUUGGGAUAAUCCAAUGGUUGUGUGCAGAGAGAACAGCGACACAAGAGUCUUCCAGCUUUUACCACCUUGUGAAUUCUAUGUAUUUAUUAUUCCCUUUGAAAUGGAAGGGGACACAACAGAGAUACCCGGGGGUCUUCCAUCUGUAUAUCAGAAAGCACUGGGUCAAAGAGAACAGAAGAUACAGAUCUGGCAGAAAACUGUGAAGGAGGCUCAUUUGACAAAGGAUCAAAGGAAGCAGUUCCAGGUACUGGUAGAGAACAAGUUUUAUGAAUGGUUGAUUAAUACAGGACAUCGCCAACAGCUGGACAGCCUUGUACCCCCUGCAGCAGGCUCCAAACAAGCAGCUGGAUAAGGAUCUUACAUGCAGACACUGGGCCCUGGAAAUACAAGGAUAAAUGGAGGAUGGUGCUCAUCUUGAAACUUGAAACUAAAUUGGGAAGGUGCUAUUGCUGCUUAAGAGACAUUGGGACUUUUCUGUCUUUUUUUUUUUUUUUUUUUGAGGCAGAGUCUUGUUCUGUCGCCCAGGCUGGAGUGCAGUGGCGCGAUCUCGGCUCACUGCAAGCUCUGCCUCCCGGGUUCACGCCAUUCUCCUGCCUCAGCCUCCUGAGUAGCUGGGACUACAGGCGCCCGCCACCACGCCCGGCCAAUUUUUUUUGUAUUUUUAGUAGAGACGGGGUUUCACCGUGUUAGUCAGGAUGGUCUCGAUUUCCUGACCUCGUGAUCCGCCCAUCUCGGCCUCCCAAAGUGCUGGGAUUACAGGCGUGAGCCACCGUGCCCAGCCUUCUGUUCUAUUUAAGAACUUUGAUUUCCAUUCCAUUUUCAUUUAUUACUGUUUAGGCCGAAUUUUCGCUAAACUUCUGACUUUCAUAUAAACAUAUUGCUUAUAGAACAUCAGAAGACUCGUCUUUGUGAUGCCCAAAUGAAAAAGUUGGUGAAGGUAGUACCAUUGUAUGUAUGUUAAUAUUAAAGCAACUGAGUGUAGAUUUGCAACUAUAGUGUGUAUCUUCAUUUGUGUGAUGAAAGAGUUUUAUUCUUUCUAGAGUUAAAUAAGAGUUUUAUAGUUCUUUGUAACUAUUUAAAAGGAAAUUGCUACUCCUUUUAAAAAAUAAUUGGAAAGGAAGUAUGAUUUGUUGGUAUAUAGACAUAGAAAUAGUUUUAUACUAUAUUUUAGUCCUUAAAGUAUGGAACUUAAUGAAAUUGUUUAAAAAAAUCUUUAUUUUUCACUUCCUGCUUCAAAUUUUCAAUAAACAAACUCUAAAGAA